AUUUCCGGUGCAGCACUCAGAGACGCGAAGCCCAGGCCACGACAAUCACCCCUCAGGUACCGAUGUUUUCAGAAACCCUCAAACAGAUUGGGUAGCGCUUCCCUGGGGGCAGGUUUCUGGGCAGGUGCCCAGACGCGCCUAGAAGCUGACCCCGGCCCUCCCGCUCACUUCCGUUCCAGGCCGCAGAGACGCGAAGUCCGACCACGACGACGACCCCUCAGGUACCGAUGUUUUCAGAAACCCUCAAACAGAUUGGGUAGCGCUUCCCUGGGGGCAGGUUUCUGGGCAGGUGCCCAGACGCGCCUAGAAGCUGACCACGGCCCUCCCGCUCACUUCUGUUCCAGGCCGCAGAGACGUGAAGCCCGGGCCACGACGACGACCCCUCAGGUACCGAUGUUUUCAGAAACCCUCAAACAGAUUGGGUAGCGCUUCCCUGGGGGCAGGUUUCUGGGCAGGUGCCCAGACGCGCCUAGAAGCUGACCCCGGCCCUCCCGCUCACUUCUGUUCCAGGCCGCAGAGACGUGAAGCCCGGCCACGACGACGACCCCUCAGGUACCCAUGUUUUCAGAAACCCUCAAACAGAUUGGGUAGCGCUUCCCUGGGGGCGGGUUUCUGGGCAGGUGCCCGUGUUGAACUCAGUGUGGACUUGCGGCGUCUUGCGGGCCUGUAGAUUAAUAUGACAGCCGUGAUUCCACCCUGCUUCACCAACGCACAUGCGUUUUCUCUCCUCUUAGGGGCCCUGUUUUCUGUUACAAUGGAUCGAGAUUUAGAACAGGCUCUGGAUCGCACAGAGAAUAUCACUGAAAUUGCCCAACAGAGACGUCCUAGAAGGAGAUACUCACCUAGGGCGGGAAAAACUCUGCAGGAAAAACUUUAUGACAUUUAUGUUGAAGAAUGUGGAAAAGAGCCUGAGGAUCCUCAGGAAUUGAGAAGCAAUGUAAACUUGUUAGAAAAGCUUGUUAGGAGAGAGUCCUUGCCAUGUUUACUGGUCAAUCUAUACCCAGGCAAUCAGGGGUAUUCUGUGAUGCUCCAGAGAGAAGAUGGGUCCUUUGCAGAGACCAUUCGGCUGCCUUAUGAAGAAAGGGCAUUGCUGGACUACUUGGAUGCAGAAGAAUUACCCCCUGCUUUGGGUGAUGUCCUGGAUAAAGCUUCGGUUAACAUUUUUCAUAGUGGGUGUGUCAUAGUAGAAGUUCGUGACUACAGGCAGUCCAGUAAUAUGCAACCUCCUGGUUACCAAAGCAGGCAUAUUCUUCUACGUCCAACCAUGCAGACUUUAGCCCCUGAGGUGAAGACGAUGACAAGAGAUGGCGAGAAAUGGAGCCAGGAAGACAAAUUUCCUCUUGAGAGUCAACUGAUCUUAGCGACAGCUGAACCACUGUGUCUUGAUCCUUCUGUAGCAGUUGCCUGCACUGCAAACAGGCUGCUGUACAACAAGCAAAAGAUGAAUACCGACCCGAUGGAACAGUGCCUCCAGAGGUAUUCGUGGCCCUCUGUAAAGCCACAGCAGGAGCAGUCUGACUGUCCACCUCCUCCUGAGCUGAGAGUGUCGACUUCUGGCCAAAAAGAAGAAAGAAAAGUAGGUCAGCCUUGUGAGCUGAACAUUACUAAAGCGGGAAGUUGUGUAGACACGUGGAAAGGCAGACCCUGUGAUUUGGCCGUGCCUUCAGAAGUGGAUGUGGAGAAACUUGCUAAAGGGUAUCAGUCCGUCACAGCUGCUGACCCACAGCUCCCAGUCUGGCCAGCCCAGGAGGUAGAAGACCCUUUCAGACAUGCAUGGGAAGCUGGCUGUCAGGCCUGGGACACCAAGCCAAACAUCAUGCAGUCGUUUAAUGAUCCGCUUCUCUGUGGUAAAAUACGGCCACGUAAAAAAGCCAGGCAGAAGAGCCAGAAGUCUCCCUGGCAGCCCUUCCCAGAUGACCAUUCAGCUUGUCUCAGGCCUGGGUCAGAGACUGAUGCUGGGAGGGCAGUGAGUCAGGCCCAGGAAUCGGUGCAGAGCAAAGUCAAAGGUCCAGGCAAGAUGUCACACAGCUCCAGUGGCCCAGCCAGUGUCAGUCAGCUCUCUUCAUGGAAAACACCAGAACAGCCUGAUCCUGUGUGGGUCCAGUCUUCAGUAUCCGGGAAGGGAGAGAAACAUCCACCUCCCCGCACCCAACUUCCCUCAAGCUCAGGAAAGAUUUCCUCAGGUAACAGUUUUCCCCCACAACAGGCAGGCAGCCCUCUUAAGCGUCCAUUUCCUGCUGCUGCUCCUGCUGUAGCUGCUGCUGCUCCUGCUCCUGCUCCUGCUCCUGCUGCUGCUCCUGCUUUAGCUGCUGCUGCUGUGGCGGCGGCGGCCGGUGGGGCGGCACCAAGCCAUUCUCAGAAGCCCUCUGUGCCUCUUAUUAAAGCUAGCAGGCGCCGUCCAGCUGCCGGGCGCCCCACCAGAUUCGUAAAAAUAGCCCCAGCCAUUCAGGUCCGGACAGGCUCCACUGGCCUAAAGGCCACCAACGUGGAGGGCCCAGUCCGGGGAGCCCAGGUUUUGGGGUGCAGUUUCAAGCCUGUGCAGGCCCCUGGCUCGGGUGCCCCCGCUCCUGCAGGAAUCAGUGGCAGUGGCCUUCAGUCCUCAGGAGGUCCACUACCAGAUGCAAGGCCCGGUGCAGUGCAGGCAUCUUCUCCAGCACCCCUUCAGUUUUUCCUAAAUACUCCGGAAGGUCUCAGGCCUCUGACACUCCAGGUUCCGCAGGGCUGGGCGGUUCUGACCGGCCCGCAGCAGCAGUCCCAUCAGCUGGUUUCCCUGCAGCAGCUCCAGCAGCCCACAGCUGCUCACCCUCCUCAGCCAGGGCCACAGGGUUCCACACUAGGUUUGAGCACGCAAGGGCAGGCCUUCCCUGCUCAGCAACUUCUUAAUGUGAACCUCACUGGAGCAGGUAGUGGUCUGCAGCCCCAGCCCCAGGCUGCUGUGUUGAGUCUGCUUGGCUCUGCCCAGGUUCCUCAGCAGGGUGUCCAGCUCCCCUUUGUCUUGGGGCAGCAGCCACAGCCGCUGCUGCUGCUGCAGCCACAACCACAGCCACAGCAGAUCCAGCUCCAGACACAGCCUUUGAGAGUCCUGCAGCAGCCAGUGUUUUUGGCAACAGGCGCUGUUCAGAUAGUGCAGCCACAUCCAGGUGUGCAAGCAGGGAGCCAGUUGGUAGGUCAGAGGAAGGGAGGCAAGCCAACCCCUCCAGCUCCCUGAGGCUUGUGGUAGUUUGUUCUCUUUUAAAAGCAUGGGAGCACUGACCCACAUGAAUUCCCAGUUUUUACUUGAGUUUUGUUUUUUUUCUCAUGUUUUGGUAUUUUACAUUUUAAAAUACACACUUUACACAGAAGCACAAUCCACCGAUUUUUAUUUAGAAACAGGAAGUGAUUUCCUAAAGGGGCAUUGUUUUGCUUAAGUUACUCCUUUUGUUGUCAUUGCUGUUGAUAUAAUUGUUUUUAAUAUAGUAUUUUAAAGUGUCCAAAUCCUAACCAGGUUGAGUUUAAACUUGUGAAGCAUAUUUCUCUAGAGCCAUAAAAUGGCAGUACCAACAAUGUUAAGUUAAUAUUUUAACAAGAUUUUAAUUUUAAGUUAAUAUUUUAACAAGAAGAGCGCAAUUUAAAAUUUUUAAUGGUGAUAAAAACAUAUAAUCUAAAAUGGACCACCUUCACUAUUUUAAGUGCCCAGUGCAAUAGUAUUAAGUCCACCCCCACGGUUGUGCCGCAGAUCUCAAGACCAUCUUGCAACACUGAAACUCAUGCCCAUUGAACACCAGCUCCCCAUUCUCCCUCAUCCAGUCCCUGGCAGCCAUUGUUCUACUUUCUUUCUCUAUGAGUUGACUACCCUGGCCAUUUCAUGGAAGUGGAAUCAUAUGGCAUUUGUCACUUGGUGAGUGGCUUAUCUCACUUGGCAUAAUGUCCUCAUGAUUUAUCCCUGCUGUCUCAUGUGAUGUGAAGGUCAUUGCUUUUUAAAAAUGGUCUCACUGUACAUAAUAUAUAUGAAAGUGACCUAUAAACUCUGAGAAACCUCUUUCAGAAGAAAGAGUGUAAUCGUAUUCACAUUAAUAGGUUUAUGCACAAUAUAUGGAAUGGAAUUAUUACACAUUCAUUUUGAAAAAUGAAAAAAAAGUACAGUACAGUGAUGCUUGUCACACUGCGAUUGAAUACAUGGGAGACCUCUAAAGCUGUGGAAUGGAAUUAGUGGCAGAUUUGCUUGUGUGACAGUCCCCUGCCCUUUCAAAGGCCCUGUCUGCACCUAGUGCUCCACAGAGCAAGGCUUUCUCACUGGCUUUGAAAAGGCUCUUUUUGGAUGUUUUUUUUUUUUUUUUUUUUUUUCUUUUUUUUUUUAUUUUUAUUAUUUUUUUCUUUUUUUUUUUAAUUUUUUUUUUUAAUUUUUUUUUUUUUAUUAUACUCUAAGUUUUAGGGUACAUGUGCACAUUGUGCAGGUUAGUUACAUAUGUAUACAUGUGCCAUGCUGGUGCGCUGCACCCACUAACGUGUCAUCUAGCAUUAGGUAUAUCUCCCAAUGCUAUCCCUCCCCCCUCCCCCGACCCCACCACAGUCCCUUUUUGGAUGUUUUGUGUGCUCUCUUUAUAAAAUCAUUUACAUUUUUUGUAGGUUGUUUGCAAGAAACAUUUAGUGAAACAUUUGAAAAUCCAUUUUAUUGGUUUGCUUUUCAAAUAUCUGUAGCCUUGUUUCUUAAGUAGAACCCCCGUCUUUUUCUUUGUCUUUUUCUCUUUGUUGAUGCAUCAUCAUCAGUUGUUCAGCUGUUUCUGCUCCCUCAUUUUUUCCCUUGUUCCAGUGAGACUCAAAGAACCAUGAACUUUUGUGCCCCUUUGUCUUCCCUUUCUUUUUUCUUUUUUAACAACUAAGGGGUAAUCACAGAACAACCAACCAUUGUAAAGUACAAUUGUAAAGUGGCAUUUAGUACAUUCAUGAUGUUGUACAACUACCCCUUCUGUUUCCAAAACAUUUUCAUCACCCACCAAGCAAUCUCUGUACCCAUUAAGCACUAGCGUGACAUCUUCACACUCCCAGCCUCUGGCAACCACCAAUUUGCUUUCUGUUUCUAUGGAUUUACCUAAAUAUUUCCUGUAAAUGUAGUCAUACAGUAUGUGAUCUUUUGUGUCUGGCCUCUUUCACUCGGCAUAAUGUUUUUGAAGUUCUUCCAUGUCGUAAAAUGUAUUGCUAAUUCAUUCCUUUCUGUGGUUCGAUAACAUUCCAUUGUUUGUAUAUAGCACAUUUUUGUUUAUUCUGAUGAUGGACACUUGGGUUGUUUCUACCUUUUGGGCGCUGUGCAUAGAGCUGCUGUCAACUUUCAUGUACAAGCAUCUGUUCUAGCACCUCAUAUUUUGCUCUGUUAAAACCUUGAAGGGUACCCUAUGUAAUAUUAGUUUUUCUAGGUACACAUGUACAUUUCUCUGUUUUUUGCCUUAACAAAAUAGAAGGAGAUUUGAUCUGGCAUUCCAAAAGACAUCAGUAAAGAGACAGGUAUCCAGUGAAUCUUACUUGAUGAACCCUUUUACUAAUGUGCUACCGAUGCUGUUAAAGAUUUGACCAACUUCAAGCAAACACGUCGAAUUUCCUAAGUGACACCAAGUCCAUCAGAGCAGCCUGGACAUAAUUGGGAAUGGUGCCUGCACUUUUAAGAGGCGAACGAGUGCAAUGACCAGUUGUAGAGAAGAGUUUAUGCAUGGCCUUCGGAGCUAAGCAGUGACCUGAAUUCAGUAUGUCACCAAAUUUGGUGUGCUUUCUCCUUUGCCUGCUGCUUCUUUCAAGUAGGACAUGGAGACAACAGCCAAAUUUGUGCUUCAGUGAUGUGACCUUCCCUUCCCAGGCAGGCAAAUAAAUUUAGUUUUGUUUCUGAUUAUCA